CCCCUUUCUGCUGUUACCGGGAGCGCGGUGGCCACGGAACGCUGCCCGGAGCCGCGCGAGGGAGGACCCGACGCGCGGCGUUUACCCAGCGCAGCGUUCCACCGCUCGGGUUUGGCUGGAUAAAAUAAAAAAUGGGGAUAUUGACCUCCUGUCACUACUGCAUGGACUUUGAUGGUUUCCAAUCAUUACUUUCUCCUCUGUGUCAAUCUGCCUCUUCGAGAAAUUCAUACUCCUGAAUAGCUCUCCAGACCCCCAGCUGGCCAUGUGGUGAGUUCAGGGCCCAAAUCAAGUAGUACCAGCAAUCAGGGAACUCCUAUCUGUUUUGAAUGGAUUCACACCAGCCACAAGCCUGGAAAGAUGGUGUCACAAUCUACAGUCAGGCAGGAUUCUCCUGUGGAGCCCUGGGAAGGGAUCAGCGAUCACUCUGGCAUUAUUGAUGGUUCGCCCAGACUCCUGAACACUGACCAUCCUCCUUGCCAAUUAGACAUCAGGCUCAUGAGGCACAAAGCUGUCUGGAUUAACCCCCAGGAUGUGCAGCAACAGCCGCAGGACUUGCAAUCUCAGGUGCCAGCAGCAGGGAACAGUGGGACCCAUUUUGUGACAGAUGCUGCCUCUCCCUCAGGCCCUUCACCUUCGUGCCUCGGGGACUCCCUGGCAGAGACAACGUUGUCUGAGGAUACCACAGACUCCGUUGGCAGCGCUUCUCCCCAUGGCUCGAGUGAAAAGAGUAGCAGCUUCUCUCUGUCCUCAACAGAGGUACACAUGGUCCGCCCAGGAUACUCUCAUCGGGUGUCUCUGCCCACAAGCCCUGGGAUUUUGGCCACCUCCCCAUAUCCUGAGACUGACAGUGCUUUUUUUGAGCCUUCCCAUCUGACAUCUGCUGCUGAUGAAGGUGCUGUUCAAGUCAGUAGAAGAACCAUUUCUUCGAAUUCCUUCUCACCAGAGGUAUUUGUGCUGCCUGUUGAUGUAGAAAAGGAAAAUGCCCACUUUUAUGUUGCAGAUAUGAUUAUAUCAGCAAUGGAGAAAAUGAAGUGUAACAUUCUGAGUCAACAGCAGACAGAGAGCUGGAGUAAAGAAGUCAGUGGGUUACUUGGGAGUGAUCAGCCUGACUCUGAAAUGACUUUUGAUACCAACAUAAAGCAAGAGUCUGGGUCUUCUACUUCUUCAUACAGUGGCUAUGAAGGUUGUGCUGUGUUACAGGUCAGCCCAGUGACUGAAACACGUACUUACCAUGAUGUGAAAGAGAUUUGCAAAUGCGAUGUUGAUGAAUUUGUUAUUUUAGAGCUUGGAGAUUUUAAUGAUAUCACAGAAACCUGUAGCUGUUCCUGCAGCUCCUCUAAGAGUGUCACUUAUGAGCCAGACUUCAAUUCUGCAGAACUAUUAGCCAAAGAGCUGUACCGCGUGUUCCAGAAGUGCUGGAUACUGUCAGUAGUUAAUUCUCAGCUGGCAGGUUCCCUGAGUGCAGCUGGCUCGAUAGUCGUAAAUGAAGAGUGUGUCCGAAAAGACUUUGAAUCCAGUAUGAAUGUAGUACAGGAAAUUAAAUUUAAGUCUAGGAUCAGAGGGACUGAAGACUGGGCUCCUCCUAGAUUUCAAAUCAUAUUUAAUAUUCAUCCACCACUCAAGAGGGACCUUGUGGUGGCAGCCCAGAAUUUUUUCUGUGCCGGCUGUGGAACUCCAGUAGAGCCUAAGUUUGUGAAGCGGCUCCGGUACUGCGAAUACCUAGGGAAGUAUUUCUGUGACUGCUGCCACUCAUAUGCAGAGUCGUGCAUCCCUGCCCGAAUCCUGAUGAUGUGGGACUUCAAGAAGUACUACGUCAGCAAUUUCUCCAAACAGCUGCUCGACAGCAUAUGGCACCAGCCCAUUUUCAAUUUGCUGAGCAUCGGCCAAAGCCUGUAUGCGAAAGCCAAGGAGCUGGACAGAGUGAAGGAAAUUCAGGAGCAGCUCUUCCAUAUCAAGAAGCUGUUGAAGACCUGUAGGUUUGCUAACAGUGCAUUAAAGGAGUUCGAGCAGGUGCCGGGACACUUGACUGAUGAGCUCCACCUGUUCUCCCUUGAGGACCUGGUCAGGAUCAAGAAAGGGCUGCUGGCACCCUUACUCAAGGACAUUCUGAAAGCUUCCCUUGCACAUGUGGCUGGCUGUGAGCUGUGUCAAGGAAAGGGCUUUAUUUGUGAAUUUUGCCAGAAUACGACUGUCAUCUUCCCAUUUCAGACAGCAACAUGUAGAAGAUGUUCAGCGUGCAGGGCUUGCUUUCACAAACAGUGCUUCCAGUCCUCCGAGUGCCCCCGGUGUGCGAGGAUCACAGCGAGGAGAAAACUUCUGGAAAGUGUGGCCUCUGCAGCAACAUGAUGCCCCUGAGUACUGUGAAAAAGACUGUUCAACAUGCCUUAUGAUAACACCGAUUUGUGUCUAUUAUUGGUGACAUUGUUUUAGAUAUUGGGUAUUGUAUAUUAAGGAAAAAGAUGGUCUAUAUUCUCUUUAUUGCAUAUACUUAAUGUUUCAAAAGAAUGCAGAUUCUGUGUUUAAGCACAGGGCUGAUAGUUGUGGUUUUGUUUACAAAUGUUCUGUUUUGGCUGCUAUUGGUUUUUUAAAGAGGUUUUUUAUACUUUUGUAUUUGAAUAGUUAUGUUUCACUGAUGCUGAGCCAGUUUGUAUGUGUGUGCAUAUAUGUGAACUGUAACUGACAAGAUGAAUUACUCAGUUUCUCUUUCUCUAAAGCUUGUUUGAUGAAACUGGUUGGUCCUUUCAGUGAACAAAAAUAUGACCCCAAAUCUGUUUGCUCUGGCUUUUAUUUCUUCAGGAAGCAGACUUCCACUUAAAUGCCAUUUUGUGAUUGUGUCAAUCAUACACAUUUUAUUUACUUCAGAGUUUGAAUAGAGAGUACACAUUUCUUCUGCAGAUUUAUUUCAUGAUGAGUUUGAGUUGCUUAGCAGGGCGUGUGGGUCCCGUUGAAGUGCAGUUUGAAGCAACUGCUUCUAGAUGGCACUCUUUCAGGUGGCACAAAUUGAACCUGUAUUUGUCAUCUCUGUUCCACACACUGCAAUGUCAAGGGAUGCAGAAGUGAGUAGAAUUCCAUCCCUGCCCUUGAGGAUCUUGCUUUAACAGAUGUAAAACUGAACAUAAGGUAUUUGCAGAUUUAAACGAACUGGGGGAAAUAAUGAACAGUGUGAUUCUAGUAAUAACAUUAAAAUCAUAGACAUUGACUAAUAAGGUUAAAUGAAUCACAAAACCUUUAUGAAUUUCUUUUUUCUAAUAGUUCUUAUAUGUUUUCCUGAAACAUGUGAGCCUAUUCUUUUUUCUUCUACUUUCUAUAUACUUUCUCCCACUUGAGAAAGGGGCCUUGAGGCUGGGUCCCUUCAUGGUAUACCUUUAGACUGAACGGUUUGCAACCUAGGGCUUGGGCAUUACAUUCCCUGGGAUUCACAUGCCCUAACUAAACCUACCUUGAUUUUCUCAGACAGCACAGGCAGGCAAUAAAGCGUCACAGAUUGUCCCCUAACCCCAUCCAGCCAUGUGUAUGAGUGUGUUUUAUUCAAUGGGAUAGUACUGAGCACAUGAAAGAAAUGAAUGACUUCUGUCAAUCUCUUUUCAUUCAGUCUUCUCAUUCUGUCAAUUGUUUUCUCAUCCGCAGUGCCUCUGCCAGAACUGUGCUCACAUCCAUUAUUUAAGCCAGAUCUUUUCUAAGUAUUAUAGAAGUGUAGAGGCACAUAGAAUAAAUAAAACCAGACUUCAAACAAUGUUUCAUUCUUGCCCAUUGCUCCUAUUCCCUGUUAAGAAUCAAGGGUAAGAGUGGUAUGUUCACAUUCCUUUCUGAGGCAGAUGUCUAUAUCUCCAUUUACAGGCAAGGAAACUGAGGCCUAGAGAAGAGAAAUAACUUUCCUAGGUUCCCACAGGAAGUGCAUGAUGGAGCUGGGGUUGACAUUCAAGUCCACCUGCCUCCAAAGCCCAUGCUUAGGCCCUGCUUCUUUUGUGGUGUCUUUUCAAGACAAAGGAGUAAAAACAACCUUAACUGGUAAGUGUUGCUCCAACUUGCAGAAGUGGCAUUGGGCAGAGUGUUUUCUCACAUCAGUGUUGAUUUAAGGCAGCUGCUAUGGCUCAAGCAUUGCUUGAAGGGCUCUGUGCUCAGGGUUUGUAUGUUUGUAAGGCACUGAUGAGCCUGUGUGUGUUACAUAUCUUUGAUAUUAAGGAAGAGUGCACAGCAGUUGCCAGGAAGUGAUGCUUUUGAUUUUCUAUUUUGAGGAAGAAUGAGGUCAUUUAAAUAACUGCAGUAUGGGAUUUGUCUGAGACUUUGUUCCUCUCCAAUGUGAUAAUAGAGGCUUCUUCCCAGGAAGGCACCUGUUAGGGAAGUGAUCUUCAGCCCACAUGGAGCACCCCAUAAGGAAGUAAUUAGUUGUGGCAUAUAUAGCUGUUUAAUGGGUCUUCCUGAUUGUGUGGGUUUUCUGUUCAACUCUUCCUUGGCUGCCGGAAAGAAGAUGAAUGCUUGGUCAGACCAUUACCCACUGUGAGGCAUCAGUUGCAGUGCUGUAAAGGUCAGUGAUUCAUUUUCUGCCUCUGCACUCUUCACAUGGGCAAUUCCAGUAGUGUGUCAUUUACAGUCAUGAUUCUCAACUGCAGGGAGGAAGUUACACCAUCUCAAGGCAGAGGCUAUAGGAUGAGGAGGAGCAAGCCAUCCCAAAGAUGUCUGGUGUGUUGACCUGGGUGAGAAUUAUUGGCCACAACUUCAGAUUAGAUCCCAAAUAUGCCACUUUCUACCUACCCAUGGUGACUUGGUGCUCUAGUUUGGCUUGUUUGACUCCUGCAAACCUCAUGGUGAAAUUUGAUCCCCAGUGUUGAAGGUAGGCCUAAUAAGAGGUGUUUGGGUCAUGCGGGUGGAUCCCUCAAGAAUAGCUUGGUGGCACCUUUGUGGUGAUGAGUGAGUUCUCACUCUUAGUUCCCAUGAGAGCUGGUUGUUAUGAAGCCUGGCACCUCCCUGCCCUCUCUUUGCCUCCUCUGUUUCCAUACAAGGGGAGUCUGCACACGCAGGCUCCCCUUCCCCUCCACCAUGAGUGGAAGCAGCCACAAGUCCUAACCAGAAGCAGAUAUUGGUGCGAUGCUUGUACAGCCCGCAGAACCAUAAGCCAAAUUAACCUCUUUUCUUUAUAAAUCACCCAGCCUCAGGUAUUCCUUUAUAGCAACACAAAUAGACUCAGACACUGGGGAAGCCAUUUAAAUUAUCUAAGCCUCUGUUUGUAAAAUGAGGGAUAUGACUCUCUGCAGUUGAGAUAAGGAUUAGAAAUGAAAAUGAAGCACCCACUAAAAGGCCUGGUACAAGCAAGGGCAAAUGGUAAUAAUGAGGUCUAGACAGAUUACAAACUGAGUCAUACCCCUUAUUUUCUGUAUCUCUGGGUAAGUUACUCCCUGGGUCUCAGUUUAUAAUCUGUAAUACAAGGAUUAGAACAAUAGCUACUGUUGUGGGUUGAAUUGUGUCCCAUGAAAGAAUAUGUUAAAGGUCUAUGCUGGUGUCUGUGCUGUGGCCUUUUGGGAAGUAGGGUCUUUGCAGAGGUGGUUAAGUUAGGAUGAGGACAUAGUGCAUUAGGAUGAGUUUUGAUCUAGUGACUGGUGUCCUUAUAAGAAAAGGGAAAUUGAGAGAAGAGAGAAGAUGCAGGGAAGAAAAAAAGCAGAGGUUGGGGUGAUGCAUCUACAAGCCAAGGAGCACCAAGAAUUGCUGGCAGCCCCCAGAAGCCGGAGAGAGGCAGGGGGCAGAUUCUUCCUCAGAGCCUUAAAAAAAAAACCCAACAUGGCUGACCCCUUGAUUUCAAACUUCUGACAUUGAGAAUUAUGAGAGAAUAAAUUCCUGGGGUUUUUUUGUUUUGUUUUGUUUUUGUUUUUGUUUUUUUGAAAUGGAGUCUUGCUCUGUCACCCAGGCUAUAGUGCAGUGGUGCGAUCUCAGCUCACUUCAACCUCCGCCACCUGGGUUCAAGUGAUUUUCCUGUCUCACCCUCCCGAGUAGCUGGGAUUGCAGGCGCACGCCACCAGGCCUGGAUAAUUUUUGUAUUUUUAGUAGAGACGGGUUUUCACCAUGUUGGCAAGGCUGGUCUCUAACCCCUGACCUCAGGUGAUCUGCCUGCUUCGGCUUCCAAAAGUGCUGGGAUUACAGGCCUGAGCCACUGCGCCUGACCCUGUUGUUUUAAACCACCCAGAGUGUGGUCAUUUGUCUGAGACUUCGGAAUUCAAACCUGCUGGAAGGAACGUGGUAGACAUGUCAGGAAGGGGUUUGACAUUCAGUUUCUGCCCCCAGGUCUGAGCCUGCAUGGCUGGCUUAGCCACCGUCAGAUGCUACCUGCAGGAAGCCUUCCUGAACUCAUCGCCAAAGGAGGGUGAAGUGUGUCAUUUUUAGAAGCGUGCUUCCUUAAAACAAGCAUUUAAGGAUCUCUGUCUUUAAAUAAUUUCUCAACUGGUAUGGGAAGGAAAACCGUAGUUCCCCUUUUUCACUUCACUAGAAACUAAAACAAUACUUUUAUGAGUAAUGCUGAGGUAGCAGGCUGCAGACACAAUUGGGAAGCUUCAGCACAAACAUGAGAAAUCGAGAACCUUUGCAUCCUCGCAUAUCUGGGCAGCUCUCCAAGCCAAGGGGACUGAGGAUUGAAGAGCUUAACCACAUAGGUUAAGCAAAUUGUGUAUUUUUCCUUGCACUUUUUUUUUUUUUUUUGAGACAGGGUCUCGCUCUGUCGCCCAGGCUGGAGUGCAGUUGGCGUGAUCUCAGUUCACUGCAGCCUCUGCUUCCCGGUUCAAGCGAUUUUCCUGCCUCAGCUUCCCUAGUAGCUGGGACCACAGGCAUGUGCCACCAUGCCCAGCUAAUUUUUUUCUGUUUUUGGUAGAGACGGGGUUUCGCCAUGUUGGCCAGGCUGGUCUCAGAAGUGAUCUACCCGCCUCGGCCUCCCAAAGUGCUUGGAUUACAGGUGUGAGCCACCGCGCCCAGCCCUUCCUUGAACAUUUUCUGGCCUCUGCUUGUGCUUCCAGGCUUCUUUCUCCCCAGGGCUGCCCCCUCUUUUCUAGUCCUGCCGUGUUCCUGCCUCCAUGGUCUUGUUCUUCUUGCAUCCCUUGCCUGGGAUCAGGACUGCCCUUUCAUCCUGGAAAGAGGCCCUGCUCUGGCCUUCCUCGGGCUACGUACAUCCCCAUUGGUGAGGAGACAAAGGGCAAGCGCACCCAAAGCCCCCACCCCUCCUGUUAGAUCAAAUGGAGCCCCAGACAGAAUCCCCUGCCCUGUGGUCUCAACCCCACUUUUAGGGCUGCUCAGGUCUUUCCCCUGGUCCAGCCUCCUGAAAGUGAACUGCGCUGCUAAGACCAAGAGGCAGCCAAGGGGCAGCUGCUUGUAGGAUGGAGCCAAAGUGGGAAGAGAGAGGGGCAGGGGUUGGCCCAAUGCUAGCUAUACCUGAGCCACCAUGCUCCAGAGCAGAGCAGUGAGGAGUCAAAGAUUUCAAAAUUCAAACCUGCUUUCUCGGGUCCUGAUGAAGGGAUAUUCACCAUGGUAGGAAGAUAAAACAUAUUUCAAAUUUUAAAUACUUGGAUAUAUGGCAUGUGGACCUGUAUUUGUACUCUUGCAUGGGCUCUGCAGAUGGGAGUGGUGGGCGCUUCCCCUUUUCAUCUCCCUCCCGAUCUUGCCCAUUCUUCAGCGUACUGCACGUGCACACACAUGCUCCCUUCUCCUUACACUCUGAUAUCUGCAUUUACCUCAUUAUUCUACUGGGGACAGCUCUCUGAACUUUUGGCAGCCUUUGAUCCUUUCUAUCUGCCCUUGAAAGUCUCUUGGAAGCUAUGAGAGAGACUUUAUUCUCCCUUUGCUCCUGCAGCCCCUGAAGGUCCACAUUCCUGAGGGCCCUACCCAGCUCCCUGAGUGAUUGUUUGAAAUAGAACUACUCAGGAGUGCGGUGCCUGCAUUGGACUUUUUACAAGCAAGAAUAAACCUUUAUUUUGUUCAGUUCCUGAGAUUUUUGUGGGGCUGGUUCCUACAGUGUAACCCACCCUACUCUGACUAACAUAAGAUGUCCUGAUACCUGUUGUCCAGGGGAUGAGUACUGAGGGAACAGGUUUGUCACUGUCGUAGUCUGUUUAGGCUGCUAUAAUAAAAUACCUUACGCUAGGUGGAUAAUAAACAACAGAAACUUACUGCUAACAGUUCUGGAGGCUAGGAAGUCCAAGAUCAAGACAACAGCAGAUUUGAUGUCUAUUGAGGGACCACUUCCUGGUUCAUAGAUGGCACUAUCUCACUGUAUCCUUACAUGGUAGAAAGGAGAGAGAGCGGACCAGGCACGGUGGCUCACACUUGUAAUCCCAGCACUCCCAAAGUUGAGAUAUAUGCCUCAGGCUGAGACAGGCAUAUCACGAGGUCAGGAGAUUGAGACCAUCCUGGCCAACAUGGUGAAACCCAGUCUUUACUAAAAAUACAAAAAUUAGGUGUGGUCGCAAGUGCCUGUAAUCCCAGCUACUCGGGAGGCUGAGGCAGAAGAAUCGCUUGAACCAGGGAGUUGAAGGUUGCGGUGAGCUGAGAUCACGCCACUGUACUCCAGCCUGACAACAGAGUGAGACUUGGUCCCCCCUCCCUGCCCCCAAAAAAAGAAAAAGGAAAAGAGAGAGAGAGAGAACCCCCUGGGGUCUGUUUUACAAGGGCACUAAUUCCCUUUGUGAGGGCCUCACCCUCAUGACCUAAUCACCACCUAAAGGCUCCACCUCCUAAUACUGUCACAAUUGGGGGUUAGGUCUUCAACACAUGACUUUUGAGGAGAUAUAAAUAUUCAGUCCAUAACAGUCAUGCAGACAUCAAAAACUAUUCUACUCCUCUGAGUUAUCCAUAUUAUCUAGUAUUCCUUACAUUAAAAAAUAAAGGAAUAUGCAGAGAGAAAAAAAUUCUUUAACCUCACAUUCCUUUCCAGUUCUACCUCUAUGAUCUUCUUCACAGCAACAUUUUUGAAAGAACAGUUUUUAAUGUUUGCCAUCGCUUCCACACCUCUUUCUUCCUUUACCUACAACAAUAGCAUUUCCAUCUCAACCAUUCUACCCAAACCGUCAAGGUCACUAGCAAUAUCUAAAUUCAGUAGUCACUGUAUUGUCUUCACCUACCUCUCUACCACAGUUGCUUGCAUUCUUCUUAACAAAAGAGAAUACUGUUUUAUAAUAAAAUAUAAUAAAAUAAAAAAGUCUAGCUAAGAAAAGCUAGACUAUAAUGAAUUUCAUCAUAUUGUGGUGGUGAUUAUCUCUGUAUAGUGGGAUUAGAAUAAUUUUCAAAAAUUUUCUUUGUAAAUUUUACCAUAUAGACUAGAUAUCAUUUUAAAUAAAUGAUAGAUCAUUUAAACUAAUGACAAAUUACAGAUGAUAAAUGAGAUCAGUACUAUACAACUUUUAAGAGUAAUGGUUGCAUUUCUACUGUCCAUGCCCACAGUGGAGAAAUCAGAUUAGCUGUUGGGGACCACCUGAAACUCCAUCUUCGUAGAGUCUGAUGAUGGAGGUGCUGCCUGGUACCCAAAGCUCCUGGUUUUCUUGGUUAUUUAGUAAAUUACUAAAGACCACGUGAACCAAAAAGAACAGGGCCGGCUGUCAGAUAGACCAGAUGGAUGGAUGCAACCAUUCACCUUCCUCCUGGAAGCUUUGGAACCCGGAAACAUCAUGACAUUUGUGAUUUCUCCCCUUCCUCUGUAGACAGUGGUCUCUUUUCUUGGUCUCCUUUGUAGGUUUUCCUCUUCUUUCUCUGUCCAUCUCUAAAUAAAGACAGAGAUUCCAGGGCUCAGUUUUGCCAUCUCUUUUCUUCUCUUGGGAUGGUCUUAUCCAGUGAAAUAGCUUUGAAUGACUCUAAAUUUGUAGCUUCAGCCCAGAGGCUGGUACUCAGCAGCCCACUGAUAGCUGUGCUUGUAUUAGUAUUUCUUUACAGGCUUUUCCAUCUCAGAAAAUGGCACCACCAUAGACCCAGUCGCUUAAGCCAAACACCUAGGAGUCAUCCUUUCCCUUUCCCUCACUCCCCAGAUCCAGUCCAUCAGUAACUUCUGUCAGCUCUACCUACAAAAUAUAUCUUAGUUGAUGGCUCACCACAGCCACUGACAUUAUUACAGUACAAGCCACCAUCUCUCUCCUGAACUUCUAUUAGAUUGAACUACGUAGCAUUGCUGCUAUUUUAUAAUUGUUGAGCUACCAAGUGGCAAUUUCAUGUGUGGUUCAACCUAAUUAAAAACCUCCUAUCUCCUCUUUCCACACUUGCCCCUCUAUAGUCCAUUCUCCACACAACACCAGAAUGUUUAUAAAGCAUAAAUCAGAUCGUCUAUCUCCGUGGAUUAAACCCUCUGAAGACUUAAUUUAAAAUUAAGUUGGGUGGGUGCUGGCUCGUGUCUGUAAUCCCAGCACUUUGGGAGGCCAAUGCAGGAGGAUGACUUGAGCCCAGGAGUUUGUGACCAGCCUGUGCAACAUAGCGAGACCCUGUCUCUUAAAAAAAAAAAAAAAAAAAAAAAAACAACAACAACAACAACAAAAAGACACAAAUUAGCUGGGCACAAUGGUGUGUGCCAGUAUUCCCAGCUACCCAGGAGGCUGAGGUGGGAGGAUCGAUCGAGCCCAGGAGUUUGAGGCUGUAGUGAGGCAUGAUCCCGCCACUGCAUUCCAGCCUGGGUGACAGAGUGAGACCCCAUCUCAAAAAAAAAAAAGUCCAAAUUCUUUACCCAAGUAGGUUUCCUGUUGGGCUUGACCUGCACCACUUCCUGAGCUGUUCCUCUCUUCCCUCCAUCAGGAACCUCUUUAAAAAUUCCUCUUGCCCUUAGUAUACCCCCAAAUCUUCCCCCACUUUCCUUUGGGGUACAGUGAGUCUAAGUGAUCCAGAAUUUAGAGCCAGAAGCACUUGGAUCCUUUCACUUCUAGUCCUGUGAUUUGUGAUAAGUUGCUCAAAUUUCUUAAGACUCCGGUUUCCUAUUUGUAAAAUGCUGACAAUCUGUCUCACAAGGUUGUCGUACAGAUUAAAUGAUAUAAGUUAUGAAAAGUAUGUUUAGCAUCUUGUCUAUCACUUUGUGUAUAAAAUUCAGUGUUUUUUUUCCCCCUGG